AAAUAACAAAAACAGAAAAUAAAGUAGAAUAAAAGUUGCAGAAUCCAUUUUAAUAAUUUUCAUUGGAUUGAAAGACCCAACCAGCUACAAAACACUAGAACAAUUAGUAUUCAUAUUUAGCUGACCAUUAGCAGAAGAUGUACUAUAUAUUUGAUCCAUUUUUAUUCAUAUCUGAAGAAAGCCUAAUCUUGGAGUUUCAGAUUAACUUGAAAAAAAUAACAUUAUAGUGAAUAAUGGUGUUAGCCCCCAUUAGGUAAAUAUCUAUGAAGUAGUAGUGAUAAUGAUGAUGAUGGUGAUGAUCAUGAAAACAACAGCAACAUUAAUAAAAAUUUGUUGUAUAUCAUGUUAUAUAGUUUACAAUUCAACUUCAGAUAUUUCCUCUGGUUGGAUAUCUAUGGAAUAGGAGCGAUGUAAAUUGUAGUUAUAGUUUAUAAAAUGUAGUUACUCUUAUAGUGUAUAUACCCAAAGAGGUCAAAUGACUUGUUCAAGCCAGUAACAGCCAGACAGAGGGCUGAAACAUUAGACUUCUAAUUGUCCAUUUUAUGUUAUUUUUAUGAGACCUUCCUUUGGGCUCCAAUAUUUUCAAUCCUUACAUCUGACAAAGUAAGAGCAUCCAAGACUCAUUUGGCAAGUUUAUGUUUCAUUUCCAAGAGUCAACCUGUUACUGAAUUUGCAAUAUGUUCACUGGAUUCCUGCACAGGUAGCAGCCACAGACAUAGCCAUGUGCUGAUAGCAAUGGGGCAGGAAAGUCCUGAUUCUCAGUGGAGGACUCAACUCUUAAGGAAGUUGCCACCAUUUAUUUACUUUCUAAUCUCUCUCAAAAAUAUGAUUUCACUUGCUUAGCCUAGACUGAGCCACAGUAUGGCCAACAUAGGACCUUAUAAAGCAGUAGUUAAGCCUCUUUUGGAGAACUUCUCAGGCACAGCAUUGUUUCACAGCAUGUUAUCCUUCUGGCUACAUCCUUUGUUGCCAAGUCAACUCCACUUUCUUGCUCUAUUUACACAAAAUUAUCCAAGGGCUUUGCCUGUGUAUAAAAGUAUUCUCAGUUCAGCAUUUGAAUGCCUGGUAUAUUUUCACUGCUUAUUUUAAGAUGCUAUGUUUUAAAAUGAUUUUUUUAAUCUAAACAGAAAACGCGAAUUAUGAAAGCAAGAUGACAUCAUAAAAUUCAUUUAAUUUAAAAAACAAAGUACUCAAAAGACUGCAUGGCCUAGAAAGGCAGCAAAGGUGACUAACAAGUAUCAACUGGAUAUUGGAAUUGUGUUAAUUUCCUAGAGCUGCUAUAACAAAGUACCAAAUACUGGGUGGCUUAAAAUAACAUAAAUGUGUUAUUUCAAGUUUCUGGAGGUUAGAAGUCUGUAAUCACGUGUCAUUAGGGCCAUGCUUUCUCUGACAGCUUUGGGGAACAUCCUUCCUUGACUCUUCUAGCUUCUGGUGUUUGCUGACAAUUUUUGGCAUUCUUUGUCUUAUAGUCACAUGACUUUCUCCCUCUGUGUCUUCACAUCAUCUUGCCUCUUUGCAUUUCUGUCUCUGUGUCAAAAUUCCCCCCUUUUUAUUUAGACACCACUUAGUGAAUUAGAGUCCACCCUAAUGGCCUCAUUAUAAAUUGAUUACGUUUGUUAAAACCUUAUUUCUAUACAAAUUCACAUUUUGAAGUCCUGGGGAUUAGGACUACUUCAACAUAUCUUUUUUGGGGGAACACAAUUCAACCCAUAAUAGAGAUAAACUGGAAAAUGUGUAGCCUCUCCAAAAGGGUAGUAGUCACCCAGUUAUAGUCUAUGGCUCUGAUCUGAAACUUUCUGAUUUUUUAAAGAGAAACUAUGUAUUUUAUGCAAAAUAUAUGUAAGUGAUUCAGCUUGUUUUAUGAUAGCUAAACUAAGCAUGCCUGAGGGUCUGACUGAGGCUUCUGCAGGCACCCAGAUUCUCUGAUUUUUUUUUCUUGAAUUUGUCAAUUUAUACAUGAGAACUAUAACCUCAAUAGGCUAUAUGAUUUGCCUGUGGCUACACAACUGUUAAUGGGAGAGCAAAGCUCACAACCUCUUGCUCCUAAUUUUGUUUUCUUCGAACAAAACAUCAGUGUCUCUAAUCCAUUCUUGCUUCAUUCGCUGUCAGUCUUCUUUUCAGCAUUUAGUUACCAUCUCAGAUCCAAUAUGUUUAGAGAAUUCUUUCUUUAACUUCUUCCCUAAUUUUACUAGAUAAUGAUACUCGAAAAAUUUACACACAUUGUUUUGGAUAUAUAUAUUCAAAACAUAUAUAUAUAUUCAAAAUAUAUAUGUUUUAAACAUUUUGAAUAAAUAUAUUCAAAACAAUGUCAAAUUUACUACAUAUAUCAGAAAAUAUGUGUGUGUGAUCAAAACAAAGAAGCUAUUUAGCUUUCCAAAUAUCUAUCUAAAUCAGAUAAAUUUAAAAAGAAUUCUUCUCUUGCUAUUUGGCUAUACCAUUUUUCUUUCUUUCAAUGUCUUUAAAAGUUGGCGUUAUCUUUCAUAUAAAUUUUUAAAUUCUACUUUCUGUUGAGAUUUUCCCCUUUUUAAAAAUAGUUCAAUUGAAGAAGACACAAAUGCAUAAUUUAUAUCAUUAAAAAGGCAAAUCAUACCCAGAAUUAGUAUCCUGAGGUUACUGUGAAGAGGAUUUGGAAAUGAUGGGGGAGCCAUAAAGGAGUUUUUGAAUCUUAAUGCCUCCAAUUAAAAAUAAAAUAAAAAGGAACUAGGGCAGAAAAACCCAAUACUUAAGAAAAUUUACCACCCAACUAAGUGACAAACUAGACUCCAAAUCCUAAAUACAAGUUGGUAUAAGUAAACCACUGGCAGAUACAAAACCUCUGUGGUGUCUUCAAGGUGGGAGGAAGGAAAGGAUGAUAAUAGCAUAUCUGUUAAUGGUGCUGAGAUUAGGAAAACCACUCAAACUCAUCACAAAAGACUCUUUGGAAACAUGGUGGGCCAACCUGAGAACAGCAGUUAAAACUGAGAAGGAGGUCUGCAGAAUACAAGUGUGAGUGAGUGGACCAUGAUGGAAUCAGUAUGGGCUGUAAAUUCUGAAAAUUCAACAAAUCGAACUAGCUCUCUUUAGUAUCAAUCUGUUACCAGAUUACUGUGUACCCUGUAGCAAAUUUUCUAUGAACUUGCAAGGAAGAGUGGUAGGCGUUAAAGUCAGAGAGACGGGGGACAGAUAAUGUAGGGUUUUGUAGGCCAGUUAAAGAGUUAGGGUGGUUCUAAAUGUAAUGGAACAAUGUUAGAGGAUUUUAGGCAAGAAGUAACAUUUAUGUCUAAAAACAUCACUUUACCUGUUGUAUGUGGUAUGGAUUGUAGAGAAAGCAAAGAAGAAGAAAAGCAUUUGAGGCAAAAGUCUAGGGAAGAGGCUGGUGGCUUGGAAUUGGGUAUGAUUACUGAAAAGACACUCAAGUGGGCUACUCUUAGGUAUGUUUUGGCAAUAGUACUUGCUAAUUGAUUGGAAAUGAAGUAUGAAAGAAUAUGGAAUAUUGGAAUACGAAAGAAAAUGGAAGAAUAUGGAAUACUGGGAUAUGAAAGAAAAUGGAAUAUGAAAGAAUAAGAUGGAGAUUGGAUUUAAGUAACAAGAUGGAUAGUGCUGCUAAUUAUUGGAACCAGAAAGUCAUCAUCAGAGUAGGCUUUGGGAAGUAGGCGGACAGACACUAAGCAUUCUGUAAUAGCUGUAUUAAGUUGGAUAUGAACCUUGAGUUCAGGAAGAGAUUAUGACUAGAUGUCUAAAUUUCAGAGUAAUCAACACAUAGAUGGGUUAAAUAUUUUGUUUUUACACAAAAUGGUGACAAUGGCUAAAUAAUGUUCUACAUUUUUAAAAAUCUAUUUAGAAAGCCUUUUUAAAAACAAUAUCACCAUUAUACAUCACCUGUUCAAUGACAUCAUGGAUUUGCCUUGUAUUCUGCUGAUGGACACUUACUUGGCUACCACGGUCAUCUUUGUACAUAUAUCUCUGCAUAUGUGUGGGUGUUCAUCUAUAGGAGAAAUUCCUAGAAGUGGUAUUGCUACAUUCAAACAUAUGUGCAUUAAAAUUUUGAUAGAUAUUGCCAAAUACUCUCCAGAACAAUAUAUAAAAAUGUCUGUUUCCUCACAUUCUUGCCAAAUUGUAUAAUCCUUGGCAAUCUGAAAAGUUUAAAAAAAAAAGAAAGCAUUUUUGUUGUUUAAUUUGCAUUUUACAGAAUAAUUAGUGAGUUUGAGCAUCUAUUCAUAUGGUUUUAAGCUAUUUCAAUGUCCUUUUCUGUAAAUUAAACUGCCUGUUUAUCCUUUGCCUAUUUUUCCAUUGAGCUAUUGUUUUUUUCUAGAUUUUUGAUUCUCUCUCGAUGGAACGUAAUAUAAAUAUUUUCUAGAUUUUUACUUGUUUUUGAACUUUUGCAUUUUUUGGCAACAGGGUUUUUGAAACAUAUUUUUAAAUGUAAGUUUGUGACUAAUGUGAUCAUAGUCAUCUAUUCAAAAUGACAACACUAGAGAUGAAGUUAUGAAAGUGGUAGGAGUUAAUAUAUUCAGCUCUCAUUCUACUGAUUUGCUCAGUGCCUUUGGGGCAAUCAUUUAAUCAUAUGCUUUCGUUUCUACCUUGUAAGAUGAAAAAUCACAAUCUUUUUCUUACCUUUGAGGAUUUCUUUAAGAAGAAAUCUAUGAAUAAAUAUAAAAACACUAUUCUGGAUGUUAAAUACUGUGAAAAUAUGAAUUUGUGCAUGUUAGGUAGGUUUGAUAACAUUGAAUAUAAGACAUUGCAAAAUACAAAGAAUUUCCAGUGUUAUUUAAUCCUUGAAGCUUUUUCUUUCUCUAGUCUCUCUCUUUUGGUCUUUCUACUUUUCCCCCUUCUUUUUCUCUGCCUCUUCUUUCUCCUUUUCCUUUAUUGUCUUGUUACAUGGGACAAUAUUUCUAUUUGCCAUUAUUCUGAUGGAGAACUGAAAUACACACUAAGCUAGACAAAUAUGUAAGAUUAUAAAGAAAAUGAAGGCCUAGUCAUCACUAGAGGCUCUGUCCUCUGUGUCCUUUUCAAAUGACAUCUGCUUGAAAGUUAAACAUGCUAAUGAAUUAUGGUAGCUAAUUGGGGAGUGGCCAAUAGAGAUGAAUAGAUGAGAGAUGUAUUCCUAACUUUGUGAAAUGGCCAAAUUAUGUGGUUGCCACAGCACUGGGGUAAGACUCUGCAACUCUGACAGCCAGCUCAAAUUAUCUUACUAACUAGCUUUAGAUUAGUGAUUUAUAAAGCUGUCUUCUUAUAAAAUAAAUGUUACAGCAAUUACUUAAUUUAAAACUGAAGCAAUCAGAAGAAUGUAGCUGUUUGAAUGAGUGAAAAAGUAAACUCACAUUGGGAUUAUGAAUGACACACUCAGUCAUAGCUUUCAUGGAUGCAUAAAAACCAAAUAUGUCAACACCACUAAAUUUUGCAGAAUGCUUAAAGCAUUUUUUUGUGUGUGAAACAUAUGUUGAAAAUUCUUCUUCUAAUUGUUUUUCAAAAUUUUCUGGCUAAGAUAUAAAAUUGUGUGACUAGUUUACUUUAAAUAACUGAGAAGGAAGGAAGGAAGAGAGGAAGGGAGGAAGGGAGAAAGGGAGGGAGGGAGGAAAUUUCACAGUCCAGUCUCUACUCUGUACCUGAAGGGACCAGGAAACAUUAUUAAGAAGUGUUUUCUCUCACACUAGGAAAUGUAUCUGUGUUAGUCUGUUUGUGUUGCCAUAAAGGAAUACUUGAGACUGGGCAAUUUAUUUUAAAAAGUUUAUUUGGCUAGUUCUUCUGCAGGCUGUACACUAAAUAUAGUACAAAUAUCUGCUUCUAGUGAGGGCCUCAGGAAACUUGCAAUAAUGGCAGGAGGCAAAGGGAAGCCAGCAGGUCACAUUGCGAGAGAGAGAGAGCAAGACAGAGAGUGAGAGGCGCCAGGGGCAGCUUUUUUUAUUUUUAUUUUUAUUUUUGAGAUGGAGUCUCACUCUGUCACCCAGGCUGGAGUGCAGUGGCAUGAUAUCGGCUCACUGCAACCUCCACCUCCCGGGUUCAAGCAAUUCUCUUGCCUCAGCCUCCCGAGCAGCUGGGAUUACAGGCAUGUGCCACCACGCCCGGCUAAUUUUUGUAUUUUUAGUAGAGACUGGGUGUCACUAUGUUGCUCAGGCUGGUCUCAAACUCCUGAUCUUAAGCGAUCCACCCACCUUGGCCUCCCAAAGUGCUGGGAUUAUAGGCAUGAGCCAUCACGCCCAGCCAGGGGCGGCUCCUUUUUAAACAACCAGAUCUUGCAUGAACUUGUUACUGAAGGGAGGGUACUUCAUGAGGCAUCUGCCCCCAUGCUUCAAACACCUCCCACCAGGCCCCACUUCCAACACUGGGGAUUACAUUUCAACAUGAGAUUUGGAGGGGAUAAAUGUCCAAACCAUAUCAGUAGGCAUAUGAUGUGCAUGUGAAUCUAUAAAUACAAACAUCACAUCAGGGGGAGGGAGGUGCCAGCCAGAUUUCUAACACUCAUUUUAAGUGGUUUCAUGUUAUCUGACUGACUAUAGAAUCCUGAAUUCUGUAAUAAUUAUAAUAAUAAUAAUGAAAGUUAUAAAAACAACAACAGAAAAACUGAAGAACUAAGCUGAUUUUCCCAGCAUUUUUUUCUGUUUUCUAACCAUCUUUUAGCAUCCAUGAUAGUUAGGAUUGCAUGGUUAAAAUGCCACGUGAUUUUAAUAAGAGCCAUUGGUAGUGUAUACCUCCGGGGCUUCAAAAUUCAUACAUUUAAUUCUCUGUUUAAUUUUUUUUUUCUGUGACACAGCCUCAGGAGGUCCUGAGAACAUGUGCCCCCUCUGCUUUAUUUUGUCAAGAAAUACACAAAGUAAUUUAUGUGAAUGAACACUGAUGCAUUCAUCCAUUCACUCAUUGUUUACCUACAAUAAGUCAACUACUGUGCUAUGUAGGUCAUGGUGAUGUGAAAUUGAAUAAAGCAUAGAGCAUUCUCUAGAAGAAUAUAUCAUCUAAGAAAAGAGAUAGUUACAUACGUAAAUUUUUACAUUUAAGGCAAUCAAUCUAAUGUGUUAGAUGGUAGCAUUUUUAUUCUUUUAGCCUAUUUUAGGAAUCAUGCAUUUUUGUAGAAAUUUUAACCCUUUCUCAUGUAUCUCUGGCAUGGUGGUGUGACAGGGCAGAGGGAAAAAGAUGGAUGCUGAUAAUGUUGAUGUACUUCCUACCAACCAAAAAAAGACAGAUGGUCUUGUUAUAGCAAAAGUUCAGGAAAGAUGGAAGGCAGGUCAUAAUGAAAACUAGCAACAGAUACAGGGGCCAUUAAAUUUGAUGCUUGUAACAUUGCUUGCUAUGAAUUUGAAACUGCCUAAGACCGGGAGUAAGUCUUGAGGACAUUGAAAAGAGGACAUUGCUAAAUGUGACAAGUUCCCUCCCUAAUGUAUUUUUUAGCUAGUCUGAUGUGCCAACCUACCACAGGCCUAUUGACAAUAGAAGUGAACAAUGGGGUGUUCAUGCCUCUUUGUAACCAUAGCCUCUCAAAGAAAACUUCCUGUUUUCUAUCCACUGGGCCGUUUUGUCUUCUCUUUGUCCUUGACACUUGUCCCCAUUUUCUGCCCAUAAGCACACUCUUUCUUUAUUCACUAGACUUUGGAAUGUGACCUUUGGAGUUCUCACUCUUUCAAGGAUUCUGCUCAGCUUUAUUCUAUUGGCUCUUUUCAAUCAGGAAUCUCAUGCAUAAAACACCCUGAUGUAAGGUACCCCUCAGAGCCAGGCAGACCUGCUUGGUCUUCAGCAAAAGAAAGGAAAUGUAUUUGGAUUGCCAAGGGCACUGCAAAUUGUGCACAGUGAAUAAUACUCUAAAGUAUUUAUGAAGGCAUACCAGAUGACCUCAUGAUGUCUCUUCUCUCCCUUGAAACUAUUCACAAACCUAAAAAUGUAUAAAUAUUUUUCCUUCAUGUUUUGUCUCUGUCUUUAUGCAUUUAGUGAAGCAUAUCAGAGGAAUUGGAUAUGGGAAAAAAUAGUGCCUUUUUAUCUUGUCAAUCCCUCAGCAUAAUUGUCGGUUGACAUAAUCUCAAAUGGAUCUCAAAUAACCUUGUUGUAGCCUCCAUACCGUAUUCCCCAAGGUAUCUGUGAAUGUAGCAUUUCCAAAAGAGGCAAAGUCUGAAUGUCCUUUAUUUCCCUUUCUUUAUAUGAAUACUAUCUUGUUAACAUUUAGUAUGUUAUUUGAAUUAUAGUCAUACCUGCCUCCAUGUCUGUCUUGUAUUUUUCCUUUUUCCUUCAACCAAGAUCUUGCUUUACUUUACAUAUAGACAUUUUUGCUUUCAUUAAAUUGAAUUAUGAUUACUCCCUUUGAAAAAAUGGUAUUUAAAAAUUAAAGAAAUAUCAAGAAAACAUUUUUUCAGAACUGUAUUUUACUUUUUAACUUGUAUAAUGGUGCUUUUAUUUAGUUUACAGUUCUCAUGUUAAAAAUUACAACUUCAUUGGCAAAAUAAUCAUCUUUUGCAUAUUGUUUUGUUUUAUAUUUGUCACUUUUCAAUGUUUUCAUCGGAGAAGUAAUAUAUUUAACUAUGAUAACUAUACACAUACAUAACUAUAAUGUAACAUAAAUAUUACACAUGUAUAAUGUAUAACAGAAUACAUUAUACAUAACUACAAUGUAACAUUUCAAAUGAAUAUUUUAAAGUACCACCUUGCAUUUGUUUUUCUAUGCAUAUUUUAAAAGGUAUAACCAUCAAAGGCGUAUGCUUUAUCUUCUGCUUUUUUCACUUAACACAUAUCCUGAGCAUUUCUCCAUACUACCAUGUGGCUGUCAUACACACUGCAUAUUGACUUUCUACUUUUCUUCUGUGAUGCUAGAUGGUCAUGAGGCUUACUUUGAACAUAAAUCACUUAUCCAUGCACUGAAAUAUUAAGGCAUGCUACUACUCAAAACUACUAAAUUGUUAAAUUGCUCAGCAUGAAUAAAAUACAAUGCCAUUAUUUGUAAUUCUGGCCUUAAUUUGGUGAUUUUUAGCUCUUUCUCACUACCUACCAUGUAAUGAGAAGCUCUUGAUAAAGUUGGUAGCAAAAACAGAGAUACAAGUGUGGGACAUAUGAUGCUGUCUGAUGACUGCCCAGAAACACAGCCUCUUCUUAGAAACCUGGCUUCCCUUGAGAUUUGCUCUAAUUUUAAUAGGAGCUGCUCAGCAGAAGGAUGUGGAUCCAAUGGCAAGAUGGAUGAUGGGUAAUUUGAGAACAACACUCAGAGAGCUCUGUGUCAACCUAUGUUAACACAAUGGCCUUAAGUUUAUUAAAACAAAAAACCAUUGGCAAGGUAGGGACCACCAAAUUAGUCACUUCUCAAUAUAAGUUUAUGGAUUGCUUACAUGCAUAGUCCUCUUUACUCCAUGAGACUCCAUCAGAGGUCUGUUACUUAAAUUGAAAUUGUUUAUUGGAUAACAACUGUUAAAUUAUUUGUCUUUAAUAUUUAACUUCAGCAUAUACAAAAAAGGGGUUUCGAAGAAGAAUUAAGGUAAAUCUCCACUGCCCUUCCAAGAAUUUGUACAAAUGCUUUCUGAUUAUGGAAAAACUAAAAUAAAGAGGAAAAAAACUCCCUAAAUAAAUCUAGGCAGUUGCCUGACUCCCUCGUUUAAUGUAACCACAUGUUUAGUAAAGGACAAUUUAUCUCAGUAACAUAAAUAUCUACAGUGUCGGUAGGAAUCCUGGAUGGUACAAAAAAAAAAAAAAAUGUCACAGACCAUCAGAAGAAAGCUGAGCCCAUUGACCUGAAAGUUUUGAACCUUGGAAUGAGAUUCAAAUAGGGCAUUGCCUAAUCCAUGUUCAAGGUGAAGAGUAGCCAAGCUAAGCUAUGCUAAAUCAUCUCAUCAAUAAACGAGGUCUUUUCCAGAAAUUUAAUUUCACUUGAUUAAUAUCUUGGGUCAACUAAGGGUUGCGUUAAAAUUCAGCAGAUAUUUGCAAUGUGGGUGGAUUUUUUUUUUUAAUUAUGUAGAGUUCUCUUAGCUUGUCAGACAAAACAGACCAGAUUUAAGACAGGCUGAGAAGAGUAUGCCAUGUUCAGAGACUUUCAAAUGUGGUCUCACAGGGAUCCUGAUAGUCUGGAACUCUAUCAUGUUUCUCUAUUAACUUCACUUGUCACCAACUCCCUUAUUUGCAUGUCUUAAGAAGAUAAGAUGUUUAUUUAUGUAGACUGAAAGAAGAGAGAACAAGAUAUUGCACAAAAGGAUUUGGUUAGAAAUUUAACUGAUUUAUGGCAAUGGUCUCCUUCUUGCUCGAUCUUAAGACAUGAUUCAUUUUUCUGAGGAAUCCUUCACUGAAAAGGGGAAACCGAUACUGGACACUGGAGACUCCCAGGUUUUGAAGGCCAAGAGAUAGGUCAAUUCUAGUUAAAAAUUGUGGUACCUAUAUGAUCUUUGUAGCACCUCAGAGUGUCAAUAUUACCAAUUGUGAUUUAUCUUUUUUUUAAUCAGUCAAAAAUAUUAAUUGGGCACCUCCUUUGUACCAGGUAUUAUACCAACUACUGUAAAUUUAGCAAUAAAAUAACUCUGUCUUUCAUAUAAUUUAUUUUUCUAUACUUUUAGAUUACUACGCUGAUUAACUGAUGGCAUAUAUUUAAAUCUUUUAGCACAGUCCUUGGCACAGAGUAAUUGCUCAAUAAAUGUUAAUUUUCCCUAUUUCUCCAAUAUACUAUUUUUUCAAAAUUCCAAAAUAAACAUCUCAAUGCACUAUGGGACUUUGGCACAUUUCGACUUAUCUUCUCUCUGCCAAAAGUAGGCUUACUAAAUUAUAGACAAGAUUAGUACUGUCCAUUUUAAAUAUAAUAUCCACUACCCAUUCAUUACAAUCUCAAAUGCCUACGCUGGCCAGUCGGGGAGACGAAUGAGUAAAGCAAGUUAAAGUAAAACUGGCAACAGUGAGGGCUGAGCAGCCAGUAGGAUGCAUGUCCAAUCCAUAGGGUGCUCCAGCCAAUUGUUGCCAUGUCGAUCAAUAGGCCCAGUGUUGUCAUAAGACCUAACUUCACAAGGGAACUAGGAAAAUAAUUUUAUUAUGUAAAAUUUUUACAUUAUGAAGUAGAGGUAACUAAUUAAUAAACAUAUACAAGCACACACAUACACACACAUGCCCAUGCAGAGAGAAUAUACCGAUUCUGUGUACAUCCAGUAAAACCAAUCUAUGGGCCACAUAUUUGUGACCUCUAUUCUAAUAGGCAUUUUGUUUAUUUACUUACCUAGAGAAUUGAUAAUAAUUAAACAUGGAUUAUAACAUAUUUUCUCCCUUCCUGUAAGCCUUUCAAAAUCUUUUCAUUCUCCGCAUGGGAUGACUGUCAACUCUAAUGAGUAUCACAAUUAUGUCUGGAGUUUUUCAAAAUAUAUUCCUGGAACUCAAGCCCCACUUAUUAAUUAGAAUCUUUGUAAUUGUAAUGAAAUAAUCUGUUGUUUUAAAAUACUCAACCAAAUUAUUCUGAUGAUGAGCGAGGCAUGGGAACUAUGAGCCUACAGAAUAAUUUUUUUAAUUGUUUUUUUCUUUAGCAUGCAAGGUUUUUUACAACCUUCUCUUUUCUGUUCCAUAGCUUAAUGUUUUCUCACCCUUGUUCUCCAGCCAUUCUAUGCUGCUUGCAUUUCCAUGAAGGUAACAUUAUUUUCAUGCUGGAUGUGUCUGCAUGUAGCGUCCUCUUUGUUGCCUUUCUCCCUUCUGUCACAGGAAACUCUUAUUCAUCUUUCAAGCACCAGGUCCAAUGUUACCUCUUUUCCAAUGCCUUUCACGCUCUGCUAGGGAAACUCGGGUAUUCCUUAUUUUGUGCUUCCAAAAAACUUUAGGCUUACCUAAGUAAAUGAUACUUGCCAUGAUAUAUUUUCAUUGCUUGUUGCCAUGUGUUUUCUCACUCACAUAGUGUCCAGCAUAUGGCAGGUUUCUAGCCAAUAUUUUGAUUUAAAAAAAAUAUUGAUCUGAAUAUAGAGUAGCAAAUGUAGUACUUUUGAUUUAUUCUUAACUAAAUUAUUAUUUCACCAUCCUAUGGGACGGUUGUUCCCUUAAGAAAAAAGAGUGAAUCAGAGCCCAUGUUUUAGGCACUUAAUUUGCAGAGCUUAGUUUUUAAAUAAUGGUUUUGCAUAUUAAUAUUUGAGCUAAGACAAAAACAAAUAAUUUAUGUUAGAAAUUAUUUUUAAAGAAUUCUGCCAUCACUUUGGAAAUACAUAAUUUUGGAAAUGCUACAAAUUACAGACUGUCCGUAGUAGAGUUUUAAUUUUUUUAAAAUGUGGAUACCUUUGUCAAAGUUUCCAUCUCAAUUUAAGUGUGCCAUGCUUAGGAGUUAGAAAUCUCUACAGAGGUGGGGGCUAGACACAGUGUGAGCGAGGUGUGCAGGGAAUCCUGUUCAGCAAACUAAUACCAGGAGACAUUUACAGUCUGUAACAGUGGCCAGAGACUCAGACAGCUUUAUUGACGUGUCAUCAGGCUGAGAAGAAAAGGCACCGCAGCAGGGGUGACAAGGACAUGUUCUGUGUGUUCAUCGAUCUGCAGUCUCCUAUGGAAAACUCCACAUGUUUCUGAAUACCUUAAGUGAUUUUAUUGAUGCAACUCCUGCCAGCUGAGAGGGGAAUUGGAGUCACCACAUUUAUUCUUCAUGUCAUGUUGGCACUCUCAUUUAAGAAUUUAAUACAUACAUAGAUGAUGCGGGAAAGGAGGGAGAUAUUAAGUAUCUCUUCAAAUCAUUUGGGUUGGGUUGCUGGGGAAAAUUACAACGCCCCAGAAAUCCAAAAGAAGUAUAAAAAUCUCUCCUCAGUACAUUAUAUGUGGCUGCUAUAAUGGCAUUUCUGCAAUCCUUUGUUACUGAAAUCCUCUACUGCAGCAGGUGAUGAAUUUUGACCUGGGGAGCUAGUCAGUGGAGCAAAACUGUUGUCCAAAAAGAUGAUACAGAAAGCUGAUAGAAUUUGAAUGCGUGUCUAGUUUGUGAUUGGGUAUGUUCAUGGAGCAGUUGAAUUAGGACAUAUCAGUAGAUCAUAGAGUCAUAGGCCUAAUCAGGACUUUGAAUAAUUAUGUAAUCCAUUUUCCUGUCUCCAAAGAGGAAAAUCCUUAUAUUGCAUGGAGAAAAUAACAAAAUAAAACCCCAGAGAUGUAUAAAUCCAUAAAGUGCAGUCAAGUUGGGUAUCAAUUUUAAUUUUUUUUACAGUCUGAGAUUUUUUAUUAGAUCCCAGAUUUAGAACUGUAUAUUAGAAUGGCAUUAUUGUGACAAUUUUUUAAUCCUAACAUCUCUAGAUUAGAUAAUGAUAUUUCACCAAUGUCACAUUUCCUGAGUGAGACUGUGGUUACAUGGAAGAAUGUCCUUUUUUUUUUUUUAAGUUCUGGGAUACAUGUGCAGAAUGUGCAGAUCAAUUUUAAUAUUUUUAAAAAAUAUAUACAUAUUUGUUUAUAAUUCCCUUGUAUCAAAUACUAGGUUCAGAAUUAGUUUCUUACAGUAACAAUAAAUUUAGAAUUUAUUGAAACCUGAAUUCAGAAAACCUGAAUCUGGUUUUCGACCUCUCUUUUCUGCAGUAUACUUUAUCAUUAAUUCAUCAGUUAUUUCAGUCAACAUUCUAUAUGCCCAGCUACGAUGCUAGGAGUAAUGUUCUCAAAGCAGUCAUCAUGGUUUAAUGGAAAACUAAGUCAAUAUUUAUUCAGAUUAUUUGGACAGCUCAAAGAAACACCUACUCCAACCUGUGUUAGGGUUAGUAAGGAUGUGAGAAACCUUAAAAAGGCUCCUUGAAGGUGAAUAACUGCAAGUUUGUAUAUUAAUAUACAUCUCACAACACAUCUUAGUAAAUCUUUAUAACCAUUGGUGACAGUGGAACAGCCCUCCCUGUUCUCAUCUAGAAGGCUCUCCUCAUCCUACAUGCUACAGACCUACACAUCAUUCCUUGCUUAUUUUUUUGGAAUCAUACCUUGCUUCCUUUUACCUAAUGAAAAACAAAGACAAAAACAAACAAACAAAAUACUCCUUUAUUGACCCUUUGCCCACCUCUAGAUGUAACCCAAACUAUCACCUUUUCUUCACAACUAACUUUUUCAAAAUAAUUGCAUACCUUUCCUUCAUUCUUCACCUUAUUGAUAAUCUGAUUUCUAUCCCUAUUAAUCCUCUGGAAGAGCUCUGAAAAAGAUCACUUAUGCACUUCAAGGAGCUAUUGAGUCAUUUUCUCUUUUGACGUCUCUGCAACAUCUGACAUCUUUGGCUACUCUCUAACUCAGGAAACUUUCUCUUCCUUUGGCUUCAGAAGUGCCUCUCUCAUCAUUCUCCUGUGGUUAUGUCCCUUUACUGUCUCUUAUAGUUUUCCUUCUUUUCACUCAUAUUAUAGGUAAUGGUAAUCUCUGGAGUUCCAUUUGUAUCCUCAUCUCUUCUCUCUCUUAUUUUUCUUCUCACAGUAUAUACUCUCUUAUUUAUUGAUUUGUUCAACUUCCAGUUUUUCAACUAUCCCUAAUAUUUUCAUAAUUCACAAAUCUCUAUUAUCCACACAGAUAUCAUUGCAGAACUAAACCCUGACAUCAAAAUUUUAUGUUGCAUAUCUUCACUUAUGUAUAUACCAUAAGCCUCUGCAACUCAGCAGGCCUAACACCGAACUUUAUACCCCACUUGGGGUGAUAUAGUUUGGAUAUUCAUCCCCUCCAAUGUUGAAAAAAAGUUUGAUCUCCAGUGUUGGAGGUGGGGCCUAGUAGCAUAUGUUUGGCUCAUGGGGACGGAUCCCUCAUGAAUAGUUUGGUGCUGUACUCACAGUAAUUAGUGAGUUAUUGCUCUAUUAGUUUAUGAGAGAGCUGGCCAUUUUAAAAAGUCUGGUACUCCCUCUCCUCUUUUGCUCUGUCACUGACCAUGUGACACUCCUGUUCCCCCUUUGCCAUUUGUCAUAAGUGUAAGCUUCCUAAGGCCCGCACCAGAAGCAGAUGCUGGCACCAUGCUUCUUGUACACUCUGCAGAACCAUGAGCCAAAUAAACCUCUUUCCUUUAUAAAUUACUUAACCUCAGGUAUUUCUUUAUAGCAACAUAAAAUGACUGACACAUGUGGCCAACCUCUACUACAGGUCCUAUCUAUCCAAGGAAUAGUACCAUCAAUUAUCUUUUGUUUGUCAGACAUAAUUAUUUCAUCUCCUUCCAAAAGCACAUCACAUUAUCUGUUGAUUUUAGCUCCUUGAUAUUUGCCUACAGAUAAGAACCAUCAGUGAGUAUUUCUAAAACCUUGACAAUUUUUUUCUCAUUAGUUUUAUUUUUUUUAAGGCAGUGAAAAACCUGAAAAUAGCUAGAAUCACAAAGAGAACUGCUGGGCUAGGACCAUGCCUGGGACAAGAGCAGAGAAAAUUAGGGUCCAUUGUCAGCACAUGUGUAGAGUAAGUAAGUCUGCUACCCAGCCUCACAGUCAUUCCUCUCUUAUCUGCCUAAUGCCUCUGAUGCUCAUUAACAUAAAGAAAACAAAUUUCAUUUGGUAACUACAAAUUAUUUUAUUUUGUUGUAACAACAGCAUUGCCUGUAUUUUCAAAGAAUACUUCAGAAUCAUGAACACAAAGAAUAUUAUUCCUAUUGUGGAAAUCUCAUGAACAGUGGAACUAUGUAAUAAAUUAAUUUUAAAAGUGAAGUUUUCUUAGACUUUCUAUCCUGUAUCAAAAAAUAUCUAAUACUCAUAUUAGAGUAGACUUUCAUUUGAUUUAGUCAGUGUUCUUUGGGCAAGAAAUUCAGUAUGUUGUACAAAUCAUAGCAGGGAUAAACAAAGGUUACUAAAAAAUGAAUUUGGAGAUAUAGGCUGGGUCCAGUUGAUGGAAAGGGCCUUGCAGACCAAUGGUUUGGUAUUUGUUCCAAGUGCAGUGAGAUGCCUCCUAAGCUUUUUGAAAGCUGAGUUGUAAUAUAAUUCUACCUGCUGGGUGAAUUCUGCUUUUAUAUGAAAGAAAAAAGACAAGAAGCAACAUAUGAUACUCCCUAGUCUUUUUUCUUACAUAUAAGAACAUAUAAGAAACACAUAUGGUAUCUAAAAUUAGAUAGCAAUAGACAUCAAGGGAAGAAAGUUUGGAAAUAUGUUUUGAAGUUAGAACUGCCAGCUCUUUUGAUGGAUUAGACGUGAUUAGAAAGGAAAAGAAAAGGAUGAAAGAUAUCUCCUAGGAUCUUUGCUUGAGCAAAUGGGUGGAAAAUAGCACCAUUUUCAUGGUGAUUUAGCCAUGUUGUUGGAGAUGCCUAUUAGGUAGCAAAGUGAAGCUAUCUAGUAAGCAGUUGUUCAUAAUGCAUCAUUAGUUGUUAUAUAUCCCAGCAGGAGUACCCUAGCCUGUUUAAGCACUUUUAUAUGAAUAAGAACAAGGUAUUCCCUCUGGGAUGACAUAGCUCUGCAGACACAAAGACCCAAAACCAGACAAUGCAUCAUGGUUUAUUUUUUAGAAACAUUUUGCUGGGCACAAACUGCAAAGUCACACUUGGUUACUCUGAUUCCUAGUGUACCUGCUUAUAUAACAUUGACAAUCAAUCAAGAGAAAAAAAUACUCAGUUCUCAAAAACACACAUUAAGUUGUUGUUUCUAGAAUGUUUUUGAGAAAUGUUAGAAUGACAACAACAAAGACUUCCAAAUCAUAGGUAUAUUCUGUAUCAGUCCUCUCUGAAUUUCACCUCUGGCCAUUUUUGCUGCGUGUCUGUGUAAAGAAGUCACAUUUUAUGGUUGAGCCAAGUUUCUGGUCCUGUUGAUUACAUUAGAGAAAUUGUGGAGGGGACAAUGGGGAAGGACAAGAUGCUUAAGAAUUAAAGGUCAUUGGGGGAAAAGGUUGAUGAAGUAGUUAAAAAAAAAGUAUAAAUAGAGAGAGAAAUCUUAAAGAGACAGUAAAGAAAAAACCGGCGAGAGUAAAGGAAAGAGCCCAUCCAAGUUGGGAUAAAAGGCUUAAUAUUUUGGCUUUAAAAGAUUACUUAUAAUUAUUAGGUAGAAAAUUUAGUUGCCAUAAUAUGUAAUUUUUGCUUCCUCUGGGAUGAGAAUUUAGAGAGAUGCAGUUUAGGGAAAAACUCAAUUUGGAUGAAUUUCUGGUAGUAGGGGAAAUUAUAUAACAUACAUCACCAGGGUUUUCAACUAUGGGUAGGAGCAAGGUCCAAGUCUAAAUUGUGAACCUCCAAGCCAGAAAUUCUGAAAGGAUCACCGUCACCCUAUGUUAAUUGCAAAUGAACACAUCUCUAGCAGAGUGAAGCUCCUACUUCUUUCACAUCCCCCAUUAGCUACAGUUCAGCCAGUGUUUAUGCUUCUAGGUAGAGUAUUGCCAACUCUCCGUCAGGGGAAUGUCUGAAUUGCCAGUUGGCCACAGAUAUCAUGUUGCACCUCACUUUUAGGUAAUAGAAAUGCUGAGAGAAGAGUGAUUGAUUUGGAUUUAUUUGGAUUUGAGUAAUGCUCCAUGGCGCACUCAUGAAUUUUAUGAAAGAAGAACCUCACCUGGAUAUUGAAAUGGUUCUCUUUACUGCGAGGCUGCAAGGUCACCCAAUGAGAGAGGGGCCAAAUAAGCUGGAACAUCAUCUAAUACACUGAAUGUAGGAGUUACUGGAAAAGCAAGAAUAACUUAUGCGGAUUAACAAUAUGGAAACAUCCUGAGACUACUUUGGAAUCGCCAUAAAUUAAGUGGGUUCCAGUUUUGCAAACAGAGAAACGGGUCCAUGAACAAUUUGCUACAGGUAUAAAGAAGUAUCUGCAGAAAUCCAGAGCACUUAUUAAACUUCUUUGAGUUUUCUCAGGAAGAUCAAUACCUGUUGGAGAAAUUUUACUAAGAUUGGCAAACGCACUGCCUACUUACAGCAUAGAGACCCCCAGUGGAGAGCUAGACUGUUUGAAUUCCAGAAGGACCAACACCAGAUAAAUUAUGAAUGUUGAACAAGAUGACCUUACAUCCACAGCAGAUAAUGAUAGGUCCUAGGUUUAACAGGGCCCUAUUUGACCCCCUGCUUGUGGUGCUGCUGGCUCUUCAACUUCUUGUGGUGGCUGGUCUGGUGCGGGCUCAGACCUGCCCUUCUGUGUGCUCCUGCAGCAACCAGUUCAGCAAGGUGAUUUGUGUUCGGAAAAACCUGCGUGAGGUUCCGGAUGGCAUCUCCACCAACACACGGCUGCUGAACCUCCAUGAGAACCAAAUCCAGAUCAUCAAAGUGAACAGCUUCAAGCACUUGAGACACUUGGAAAUCCUACAGUUGAGUAGGAACCAUAUCAGAACCAUUGAAAUUGGGGCUUUCAAUGGUCUGGCGAACCUCAACACUCUGGAACUCUUUGACAAUCGUCUUACUACCAUCCCGAAUGGAGCUUUUGUAUACUUGUCUAAACUGAAGGAGCUCUGGUUGCGAAACAACCCCAUUGAAAGCAUCCCUUCUUAUGCUUUUAACAGAAUUCCUUCUUUGCGCCGACUAGACUUAGGGGAAUUGAAAAGACUUUCAUACAUCUCAGAAGGUGCCUUUGAAGGUCUGUCCAACUUGAGGUAUUUGAACCUUGCCAUGUGCAACCUUCGGGAAAUCCCUAACCUCACACCGCUCAUAAAACUAGAUGAGCUGGAUCUUUCUGGGAAUCAUUUAUCUGCCAUCAGGCCUGGCUCUUUCCAGGGUUUGAUGCACCUUCAAAAACUGUGGAUGAUACAGUCCCAGAUUCAAGUGAUUGAACGGAAUGCCUUUGACAACCUUCAGUCACUAGUGGAGAUCAACCUGGCACACAAUAAUCUAACAUUACUGCCUCAUGACCUCUUCACUCCCUUGCAUCAUCUAGAGCGGAUACAUUUACAUCACAACCCUUGGAACUGUAACUGUGACAUACUGUGGCUCAGCUGGUGGAUAAAAGACAUGGCCCCCUCGAACACAGCUUGUUGUGCCCGGUGUAACACUCCUCCCAAUCUAAAGGGGAGGUACAUUGGAGAGCUCGACCAGAAUUACUUCACAUGCUAUGCUCCGGUGAUUGUGGAGCCCCCUGCAGACCUCAAUGUCACUGAAGGCAUGGCAGCUGAGCUGAAAUGUCGGGCCUCCACAUCCCUGACAUCUGUAUCUUGGAUUACUCCAAAUGGAACAGUCAUGACACAUGGGGCGUACAAAGUGCGGAUAGCUGUGCUCAGUGAUGGUACGUUAAAUUUCACAAAUGUAACUGUGCAAGAUACAGGCAUGUACACAUGUAUGGUGAGUAAUUCCGUUGGGAAUACUACUGCUUCAGCCACCCUGAAUGUUACUGCAGCAACCACUACUCCUUUCUCUUACUUUUCAACCGUCACAGUAGAGACUAUGGAACCGUCUCAGGAUGAGGCACGGACCACAGAUAACAAUGUGGGUCCCACUCCAGUGGUCGACUGGGAGACCACCAAUGUGACCACCUCUCUCACACCACAGAGCACAAGGUCGACAGAGAAAACCUUCACCAUCCCAGUGACUGAUAUAAACAGUGGGAUCCCAGGAAUUGAUGAGGUCAUGAAGACUACCAAAAUCAUCAUUGGGUGUUUUGUGGCCAUCACACUCAUGGCUGCAGUGAUGCUGGUCAUUUUCUACAAGAUGAGGAAGCAGCACCAUCGGCAAAACCAUCACGCCCCAACAAGGACUGUUGAAAUUAUUAAUGUGGAUGAUGAGAUUACGGGAGACACACCCAUGGAAAGCCACCUGCCCAUGCCUGCUAUCGAGCAUGAGCACCUAAAUCACUAUAACUCAUACAAAUCUCCCUUCAACCACACAACAACAGUUAACACAAUAAAUUCAAUACACAGUUCAGUGCAUGAACCGUUAUUGAUCCGAAUGAACUCUAAAGACAAUGUACAAGAGACUCAAAUCUAAAACAUUUACAGAGUUACAAAAAACAAACAAUCAAAAAAAAAGACAGUUUAUUAAAAAUGACACAAAUGACUGGGCUAAAUCUACUGUUUCAAAAAAGUGUCUUUACAAAAAAACAAAAAAGAAAAGAAAUUUAUUUAUUAAAAAUUCUAUUGUGAUCUAAAGCAGACAAAA